CUCUUCUGGCGGUCACUCGAAACCGCCGGGCCUGAAGCGGGCGCUCUUCCAGCCUGGAGAAGGCUGCGGGUCUCCAUCCGUGGCGCCUCGCCAGCUGCAGGACGACGCGGGCUCUUGAGGGGCAGAGCAGCGCAUCAUGCAGGAUCCCAAUGAAGAUACAGAAUGGAAUGACAUUUUAAGAGAUUUCGGCAUUCUUCCUCCUAAAGAAGAGUCAAAAGAUGAAAUUGAAGAAAUGGUUUUACGUUUACAGAAAGAAGCAAUGGUGAAACCAUUUGAAAAGAUGACUCUUGCACAGCUAAAGGAAGCUGAAGAUGAAUUUGAUGAAGAAGAUAUGCAGGCUGUUGAAACAUAUAGAAAGAAGCGGUUACAGGAAUGGAAAGCUCUUAAGAAAAAACAAAAAUUUGGAGAAUUAAGAGAAAUUUCUGGAAAUCAGUAUGUGAAUGAAGUCACAAAUGCAGAAGAAGAUGUGUGGGUUAUAAUUCAUCUAUACAGAUCAAGGGUCUCACUGUGUUUCCCAAGCUGGAGUACAGUGACAAUUGUAGCUCAAUGCAGCUUUGAAUGCUUGGGCUCAAGCAAUGAUCCUCCUGCCUCAGUCCUCCAAGUAGCUUGGACUACAGGUCUGCACCACCACAUCUGGCCAGGUUUUAAAAUUUUUUUGUAGAAAUGGGGUAUUGUUAUGUCGCCCAGACCGGUCUCAAACUCCUGGCUUCAAGUGAUCCUCCUGCCUCAGCCUCCCAGAGUAUUGAGAUUACAGGCGUGAACCACUGUGCCUGGCCUGCUGUCUCAUUUUAAUGACUCCGUGGGGGUAAACAUUUAAAAGGACUUGCAUUCUUCAGAGAAAAGUUAUUUCCUGAAAUCACACUUCCAUAUUACCUAUACUAUUUAUUUGGUUAACCAGUUUGUAAAUGCUGCUUGUAGAUCUCACAAAUAAGGAUGAGAAACACGGACAUUUAUAAAACAAGGAUCUGUUUGUGGUAAAUAUUAUAUACUGAAGUGGUUUACUGAAUGUUUUUUCUGAUCCUGUGUGGUUAGCAGAGUAGAUAUGGCUUCUAAGUAAAAUUAUCUAGCUUAAUGGUUACUUCCAGAUAAAUUACUAGUUUUUAGAAAUAAUUUUUUAAAAAUUCAUAAAGAGGUUGAAUGUGAUUUAGUCUGCUUCAAAUUGUUGUAUGCUUUGAUAGACUCAAAAAGAAGGAUGUGGUUUCAUAAUACUUUAAGUAAACCUUCUCAGAAGGUUUUUCUGGGCCACUCUAAAGUAGUUACAUAUUAGUUUUCUGGACAUUAAGAAAAUACAUUCCUGGGGCUGGGUGCGGUGGCUCAUUGCCUGUAAUCCCAGCACUUUGGGAGGCCGAGGCAGGCGGAUCACUUGAGGUCAGGAGUUCAAGACC